GAUGAAAGUUUUAGACAAAGCCGAUCAAACCUCACCUCUCUAUUAGUGCAGCCCAUCUCUGCACCCCUCGUUGCAAAACUGAUCUCUUCGCCAAAAGCUAGAACCAAAAAUGAAGCGUGUAGCUCUCUAGAGCUUCCAAAUAAUGAAAUAAGAGUCGUCAGCAUGCAAGUUCAGACAGUCACAAAAUUGAAAACAGUUACUAAUGUUGUUGGAUUUGUAAUGGGCUUGACAUCUCCAGACCGGUAUAUCAUAGUUGGCAGCCAUCAUCACACUGCACACAGUUAUAAUGGACAAGAAUGGGCCAGUAGUACUGCAAUAAUCACAGCGUUUAUCCGUGCCUUGAUGUCAAAAGUUAAGAGAGGGUGGAGACCAGACCGAACUAUUGUUUUCUGUUCUUGGGGAGGAACAGCUUUUGGCAAUAUUGGCUCAUAUGAAUGGGGAGAGGAUUUCAAGAAGGUUCUUCAGAAAAAUGUUGUGGCUUAUAUUAGCCUCCACAGUCCCAUAAGGGGGAACUCUAGUCUGUAUCCUGUAGCAUCACCAUCUCUUCAGCAACUGGUAGUAGAGGUAA